AGUCAGAGAGAUAGAGCGGUCUCUCCCGAAAGCAAGAUUCCGUUUGAAAACUCUCCUAGCGCGGUGCCCGCGCCGUGACUCCGCAGGUAGGUCCGCCGAGCCUGUUCUGCGCCUCCUGCCCUGGUGGGGGCGGCCGCGGGGACUCGCAGAGCACUGGCACUGCGGGGGCGAUCAGAGGGCGCGGGCGGUUUCCCACCUGCUGCGGACCGCCGUGCGGGAGCCCAGAGAGCUCCGGCAGCUGGGUUAGGGCGCGACCCGCGCAGUGUGACUGGAAAUCUGGAGCUGGGGGCGCGCAGCAGGCGGUCUGGUGGUUCGGCAGGGGAGCCAAAUCCACCAGGGAAGGAAACAUCUGGUGGGGAGGCGGCGGCAGCUGCGCUCGGGAGGACGCCCCCUUAGCGCCCUCGGCUCCCUCCUUCCUGGGCCCGGACGGUGAGGAGAGGCCUGAGCGCGCGGAGGGGCCGCCCCACCUCCCGCGCCAGCUGCAGCGCGGGGUUGCCUUCCCACGCGCUCGGCCCAGGCCCCGGGGCCCCUAUCUCCUCCAAACUCUGUCGCUCCCCACAGGAACCAGCAAAGCGGGCCGGGGUGCGAGAGAGGCGUGGGCUUACAGCCCGGGUGGGGAGGCGGCCUCCGCGUCCGCCUGGUCUCUGGUGGCGCCAGCCCAGACCCAGCUCCGGCGCUGACAGUUACCCCGCCCCCAUCUGUCCCGCUCCCAGCCAACGUGGGUCCAAGCUGCAGCGGGACCCUCGGGACAACGCCACUCCGUUUUUCUUUUCUUCCGAGUUUCGUGGCUGUUUAAAGAAUUGGGUUUGGGGUUUGUGGCGUCUAAUUGUACGGACGAGAAGUGCAGGAAGCGACAAAGCUCUAGCCCUAGGAGCCACCCCGGAGGGAGGCGGAUGGCACUCUCACCCCUAGGGGCAUUCUGGCGCUUGGGUAGCGGGAAACUUCGCGGGAGCCCCGCGACACGUCCCAGGCGUCUUUUCUCCCAGGUCUAUUCCCAUUCCUCCGGAGAAGGGGACACAAUGGGGCUGGGGAUCUGGAGCAGGGGGCCUGCACCCUACAGGGACCAAGGCCUGUAGGACUCGUUUGAGCUGAGAGCGCCAACGGACAGACGUAGACUGUGUGGCCUGCAUCUUGCCUAGGAAGCCGAGGGGCUCCUAGUCCGGCAGUGGAAACAGCGCGAAGCCGGAGGACUGCAGGUCCUGCCCCGGCCCAGAGUUCCCAGCACCCUCGUUUCUGAACCAGCCGAGGCCACGGAGAACUGCUGUACUGCAGCUCACGUGUGAACCCGGUCACCAUCGCCUUCACCCCGGGAGGAAGGCAGAUUCGUUUACUCCAGACCACCUCGACUGUGGGGUACCGCCCCCGGAGCCGGCUGGAGCCUAGCGGCAGGCGCAGCCACGCCCUCCCGCUGCGCUCAGAUUUCGACCUGGUAUUAGGUGAACUGAUUGGGGGUUAAUGAGAGCGACGCCCCGGGCAGCUAGUUCCCUCCCGGGCCCGGGCCCGACCCCCGCUCUCUGCUAAUGCAGCCUGCGCGCUCUGGCGUCCUGUCUUUUUUGUCUGCUAAAUUGUCGGUGCACUACCGACUCGGGACACCUAGCAUUUCCCAGUCAACGUUCGUGGAUCGGGCUCCACCUCCCUAGGACAAGAUUUUUUGGUCUCCUCCGGGCUGGGGCUGAGCAAGCCCUCGGAGUGACCGUGGGUGACAGCGGCUCCAGGGACUCUUGGGGCGCAGUGGGGAAAGUGCCGGACCACCAUGCCGCGCUCAUUUCUCGUCAAAAGCAAGAAGGCUCACAGCUACCACCAGCCGCGCUCCCCAGGACCAGACUAUUCCCUCCGUUUAGAGAAUGUACCGGCGCCUAGCCGAGCAGACAGCACUUCAAAUGCAGGCGGGGCGAAGGCGGAGCCCCGGGACCGUUUGUCCCCCGAAUCGCAGCUGACCGAAGCCCCAGACAGAGCCUCCGCAUCCCCAGACAGCUGCGAAGGCAGCGUCUGCGAACGGAGCUCGGAGUUUGAGGACUUCUGGAGGCCCCCGUCACCCUCCGCGUCUCCAGCCUCGGAGAAGUCAAUGUGCCCAUCGCUGGACGAAGCCCAGCCCUUCCCCCUGCCUUUCAAACCGUACUCAUGGAGCGGCCUGGCGGGUUCUGACCUGCGGCACCUGGUGCAGAGCUACCGACCGUGUGGGGCCCUGGAGCGUGGCGCUGGCCUGGGCCUCUUCUGCGAACCCGCCCCGGAGCCUGGCCACCCGGCCGCGCUGUACGGCCCGAAGCGGGCUGCCGGCGGCGCGGGGGCCGGGGCGCCAGGGAGCUGCAGCGCAGGGGCCGGUGCCACCGCUGGCCCUGGCCUAGGGCUCUACGGCGACUUCGGGUCUGCGGCAGCCGGGCUGUAUGAGAGGCCCACGGCAGCGGCGGGCUUGCUGUACCCCGAGCGUGGCCACGGGCUGCACGCAGACAAGGGCGCUGGCGUCAAGGUGGAGUCGGAGCUGCUGUGCACCCGCCUGCUGCUGGGCGGCGGCUCCUACAAGUGCAUCAAGUGCAGCAAGGUGUUCUCCACGCCGCACGGGCUCGAGGUGCACGUGCGCAGGUCCCACAGCGGUACCAGACCCUUUGCCUGCGAGAUGUGCGGCAAGACCUUCGGGCACGCGGUGAGCCUGGAGCAGCACAAAGCCGUGCACUCGCAGGAACGGAGCUUUGACUGUAAGAUCUGUGGGAAGAGCUUCAAGAGGUCAUCCACACUGUCCACACACCUGCUUAUCCACUCAGACACUCGGCCCUACCCCUGUCAGUACUGUGGCAAGAGGUUCCACCAGAAGUCAGACAUGAAGAAACACACUUUCAUCCACACUGGUGAGAAGCCUCACAAGUGCCAGGUGUGCGGCAAGGCAUUCAGCCAGAGCUCCAACCUCAUCACCCACAGCCGCAAACACACAGGCUUCAAGCCCUUCGGCUGCGACCUCUGUGGGAAGGGUUUCCAGAGGAAGGUGGACCUCCGAAGGCACCGGGAGACGCAGCAUGGGCUCAAAUGAGCACCCUGGCUGGCUGCAAGCAGCAGCUACACAACACUACAGAGGGCAGCCUCCCUGCUUGCCACCACUCUGCUCCCUGCUUGCCUCCACUCCCUUCUGACUUUCCAGACCCCAGGUCCAGUCUGCAGAUCCUACCAGGUUGCUCCUCCUUCGCCUUACCUCCUGGAGCUGCCAGAAGAAAUGAGGUACCUUUUCAAAGUGCAGCCGAGAGUGAGAACCAAGUGACUCUCUAGGCUUCGGACACAAAUAGGCUCCUCUACACCUGAAGACAAAGGCAAAGUCAAAUGGGGACCAGAAUAAAUCUUAGACCCCACAGUCCUUCCCAUUUCCAGCCCUAAUCUACAGACAGGAAUGCCCUUCAGGUUUCUUCCCUCCCCCCUCUUGACCUACCCCAGAUAUUUGUGUGGAAGAGGAGGAAUCACCAUUUACAAGGUGGACAAAUGCUAAUAUUUUUAUCUAGAAAGAAGAGUGAGUGUUAACUUUUAUUUUUUUCCUUCUGGGGGGUCUGUUGACUCCUUUCUUUUGGGUGCUGCCUAUAAAUCUUGGAGGAAUCAUUUCUCCUCCUCAAAAACUGAUUCAGAAACUGACUUGGGGAAGGAAUUUAAUACUUUGAAGUCAUGAGAUGCACCAUCGAGGCUACCCCCAAGAAGAAGCAGAAGAGAAGUUGGUAAUGAGAGGGGAUUAGAGGUCCUCCCUUCAGUAGGGCUGUGAAAACCUCAUCACUGGAGGUAAAAGCACAAGCAAUGCCUGUGGACAAGAUGUCAUUCAUUCACUCAGCAAAUGUUCAUGGAUCACCGGCUACCAAGGUACCAGGCACCAUGCUAGGUAUUGGGGAAGAGAGACUGAAGUCACAACCCCUGACUGCUCCUCAAAAGCUAACGGUUGCACCUCCAAGUGGCUGGGUCUGUUCUUACUCUUGGAGGGAAUUCUGAGAAGACAGCACAGAAUUGUAAACCUUCCCUUUUGACCCUUUUGGAUUUUAUCAGGUGUAAACAAAAAGCUGAACAGUUACUUCAAAGAUAUGUGUGUAUAUUCAGUUUUUUAUUGUUAAGCUGAUAUUUUAAAGAUUUCUGAGCUAGCAGGCAUGUGGGAAGGAAGGCUCUGUCUUCAACUCUUUGACCCUCCAUGUGUACCAUAGAGGGGGGAAAGGUGGUAUUUUCACUUUGAUGAGGUUGGUAAAUGUUUUUAGAUCUUCUGGUAAGCAUUAUGUUUGUUAAUACAUAUUUAUUAGAGUGAUGUUUUAAGUUAAUAAAGUAUUAAGAGUAUUACAGAUUGCCUUUCCUUUAGGCAGGGAAUUUGGGGAAGACCUUUGUUUUAGUCUGUAGGGGGAAAGCUGGCACUGAAGGAAACUGCAAUGGAGUAUAAAAGUGAAGCACACAAGCUAAUAUCCAGAAGAGUAAAAUCCAAUUGCUCGGGUUUCCAUAUACUUUCUCCUUUGCUGCUACACCUCAGAGAUACUUCUUUCAUCUUCUUUCAUAAGAGAAAAACUAGGAGGUGUACAAAACUAAGCUACUACCUUGUAGAGCCCCUGAUGGUUCCACAGGCACGUAAGUAAGCUCUUUCCUCUGAAAAUGUCAACAUAUUUUUUUAGGGGCCUGAAGGCUCCCAGAUGAAUAAAGAAAUCACAGGUCUUAGGUCUAGGUUUUAGUUUUAGUCACAGCUCUGUCACCAACACAUCAUGUGACUUGUGUAAAUCUUUUGACUUCCCCGAUACUGGUUUCCUUGAUCAAGUAAUACGGAGACAGCUCUGUCAUUCCUGUCCAACCCUGACCGCUUUGAUUCUGUGGAGACUGGAAAGGAAAAAAAGUGUGAGAUUGGUUAGCUGCCUCCCCUAAUGCAAGUCACAAAUCUAAAGGCCCAUGAGGAUCUGGGUUAUUUCUGGUUCUGUCCCACCUGUGGGAGUUUUUUGCAUAAGUCAAUCCUUUAAGAGAAUGAAACCAGAAUAAAAUCCUGGCCAAAAUCCCUACUACUAGUGCUUUAACACCUCCCAGCCAGACAUUCAGGGUAUGCAUGCCCCAUGGUGAGAACCAGCAGAUUGCCCAUUUCCAACUCAAAUUGAUUUCACACAUAUAAUUGAGCACCCAGUAUGUGCUGGGCAUUCUUCUAGGGGGUGGAGAUAUAGCAGUGAGGACAAUGUCUUACGAAGCUUUAUUUAUUCAUUGUUGAAUCCUCAGUUCCCAGAAUAGUGCCUGGCACACAGUAGGAGAUUAAUAAAUAUUUACUGAGAUGUUAAGUGAAUAAACAGAAAAUAAGCUCCUGCUUCAUCCUAGGGCCUGGCUCUGCUCUCUACAGCACAAAGGGAAGAGAGAUUGCUUGACAGCCUGGGAAACAAAUAGAAUCCACACGACUUUCUCUCCAGGUUGGCAGGAAAGGGGGGCUUGAAUGCUGCUUUUCUCUGGUUUCUCCAAAUCUCAGUCCUUGGCUGUCCUCACCUGAUUUCCAGCACCAUGUCUUUCCAUGUCAGUUUACUCUCAUUCAGAAUUUAAAUUCGUUUACUCUGUAAUGGAGUUUAAGAUAGUUUUUCAGAACUGAUGGAUGAUGAACAGUUGCAGCGUCCAGGAACCACUUCCUAGUGUCCUGGGAGACAAUCCUCCCAGUGAAUGAAAAUGACAAAAACAUCCUUCCCACAGAAGUCACCCUGUGUACUGGUUGGUUAUUUCCAACCUGGUUUGAAAAGUAAAGAAGUUGCACUGAGGGGUAAGUAGAACUGAUUGAAAUCUAGGUGCCUGUGCUGUCCUGCUCUUCCCUUAUGACGUUUAGAACAUUUGGUCCAUUUUUGUUAUCCCUGUUUAUGCUCUAAGUGAGGAAUUGUAAUUUUGAUGUUAACUGUAUGCCUUUUUUUUUUUUUUUUGGUAAAAAAUGUAUCUUGAUAUCCCCAGUUCAGAAUCAAAACAAAUUACUGUGCCUGUUACCGUGUGAAAUUUGAAGAUUGCAAAUAUCUCUCUUAAUGUUAUUACUUGACUCCAUUAAAAAUAGAUUGUGAAUA